GGAAUUUUGGCGGGUUCAGCUGUGAACGAAGAAGGCGUCCCGGCAUCGGGUGAGGAGCGCGGGCCCCGGGCGUGCGUGUGACCCUCGGGCGGCGGGGCCGGGGCCGCCUCGCACGUCUCUGCGCGGGUUGCAAGGGGUCCGAGGCUAGAGGCGCGGGGUCCCGGGAGCUCGGGUGGGCGCGAUCUGGAUUUGGCGGCAGCUUGGGACCGCUCGGAGCUGGCAUGGCCGGGCCGGGGGCUGGGAGUUGCUGGCCGUCUACUAAGGAAUCGGGUUCUUCCUUUUAAACGCAGCCUUUUAAGUGCUUGCCAAGUGCCUGCCGCCUGGGCUUUCUUUUAUUCAUUCAUUCAUUCAUUCAUUCAUUGGUUUCUCGUAUUCAUGAUUUGCCAAUGAUUAUUGAAUGCGGACGGUGUGCAUGGCUCGGAUCACAUUUCCGCUGCCUUCACAGCGCUUACAGUUUAAAGGCACGAGCAGGUAGUAAACAAAUGCACGACAGUGGACGACUCAGGGUGGUCCAGAAAGUCUCAGAAAGAUGAGUAAGUGGAGACCGAAGGGCGAGAAGGACCUGGGGGGAGCUUUCUUCGACAGAGCCUGAGACCUCAAAGCAGCUUAGUGUGUUCCAGAAGGUGGAAGCGGGCUGGCCCGGCUGGAGCAUCGUUAUGGGUGUCGGGCCAAGAUUCUACAUUGCUCAUCUGGGCAUCUGAGCCUCCUUCGAAGUUUCCUGUCACAACUGUCCUCUUGACAGCAUGGAUGAGGAGGAAGACAAUCUGUCUCUGCUGACCGCACUGCUGGAAGAAAAUGAGUCAGCCUUGGAUUGUAAUUCAGAAGAAAAUAACUUCUUGACGCGGGAAAAUGGCGAGCCCGACGCAUUUGAUGAGCUCUUUGAUGCCGACGGCGACGGUGAAUCUUAUACAGAAGAGGCUGAUGAUGGAGAAACAGGAGAGACAAGAGACGAAAAGGAAAAUCUGGCCACUCUCUUUGGAGAUAUGGAGGACUUAACAGAUGAAGAAGAAGUUCCCGCAUCACAGUCAACUGAAAAUAGGGUCCUCCCUGCUCCUGCCCCCAGGCGAGAGAAAACGAAUGAAGAGUUGCAAGAGGAAUUAAGGAAUUUGCAAGAGCAAAUGAAGGCCUUACAAGAGCAGCUAAAAGUAACAACAAUUAAACAGACAGCAAGCCCAGCCCGUCUGCAAAAAUCCCCUGUAGAGAAGUCUCCCCGGCCACCUCUUAAGGAGAGGAGAGUUCAGAGAAUUCAGGAGUCAACAUGCUUUUCUGCGGAGCUUGAUGUCCCUGCGCUACCAAGAACCAAGAGGGUGGCUCGAACACCAAAGGCUUCACCUCCAGAUCCCAAAAGCUCAUCUUCAAGGAUGACAAGUGCACCCUCCCAACCCCUACAGACGAUUUCUCGGAACAAACCUAGUGGGAUAACUAGAGGUCAAAUUGUGGGGACCCCAGGAAGUUCUGGGGAAACGACUCAACCCAUCUGUGUGGAAGCCUUCUCUGGUCUGCGGCUCAGGCGGCCUCGAGUAUCCUCCACAGAAAUGAACAAGAAAAUGACCGGCCGAAAACUGAUCAGACUGUCUCAGAUCAAGGAAAAGAUGGCCAGAGAGAAGCUGGAAGAAAUAGAUUGGGUGACAUUUGGGGUUAUAUUGAAGAAGGUUACGCCACAGAGUGUGAAUAGUGGAAAAACCUUCAGCAUAUGGAAACUGAAUGAUCUUCGUGACCUGACACAAUGUGUGUCCUUGUUCUUAUUUGGAGAAGUUCACAAAGCGCUCUGGAAGACGGAGCAGGGGACUGUCGUAGGGAUCCUCAAUGCCAACCCCAUGAAGCCCAAGGAUGGUUCAGAGGAGGUGUGUUUAUCUAUCGAUCAUCCUCAGAAGGUCUUAAUUAUGGGUGAAGCUCUUGACCUGGGAACCUGUAAAGCCAAGAAGAAGAAUGGAGAGCCGUGCACGCAGACUGUGAAUUUGCGUGACUGUGAGUACUGUCAGUACCAUGUCCAGGCUCAGUACAAGAAGCUCAGCGCAAAGCGUGCGGAUCUGCAGUCCACCUUCUCUGGAGGACGAAUUCCAAAGAAGUUUGCCCGCAGAGGCACCAGCCUCAAAGAACGGCUGUGCCAAGAUGGCUUUUACUACGGAGGGGUUUCUUCUGCCUCGUAUGCAGCUUCAAUUGCAGCAGCUGUGGCUCCUAAGAAGAAGAUUCAAACCACUCUGAGUAAUCUGGUUGUUAAGGGCACAAACUUGAUCAUCCAGGAAACACGGCAAAAACUCGGAAUACCCCAGAAGAGCCUGUCUUGCUCUGAGGAGUUCAAGGAACUGAUGGACCUGCCGACGUGUGGAGCCAGGAACUUAAAACAACAUUUAGCCAAAGCCACAGCUUCAGGGAUUAUGGGGAGCCCAAAACCAGCCAUCAAGUCCAUCUCGGCCUCAGCACUCUUGAAGCAACAGAAGCAGCGGAUGUUGGAGAUGAGGAGAAGGAAAUCAGAAGAAAUACAGAAGCGAUUUCUGCAGAGCUCAAGUGAAGUUGAGAGCCCAGCUGUGCCAUCUUCAUCAAGACAGCCCCCUGCUCAGCCUCCACGGACAGGAUCCGAGUUCCCCAGGCUGGAGGGAGCCCCGGCCACAAUGACGCCCAAGCUGGGGCGAGGUGUCUUGGAAGGAGAUGAUGUUCUCUUUUAUGAUGAGUCACCACCACCAAGACCAAAACUGAGUGCUUUAGCAGAAGCCAAAAAGUUAGCUGCUAUCACCAAAUUAAGGGCAAAAGGCCAGGUUCUUACAAAAACAAACCCAAACAGCAUUAAGAAGAAACAAAAGGACCCUCAGGACAUCCUGGAGGUGAAGGAACGUGUAGAAAAAAACACCAUGUUUUCUUCUCAAGCUGAGGAUGAAUUGGAGCCUGCCAGGAAAAAAAGGAGAGAACAACUUGCCUAUCUGGAAUCUGAGGAAUUUCAGAAAAUCCUAAAAGCAAAAUCAAAACACACAGGCAUCCUGAAAGAGGCCGAGGCUGAGAUGCAGGAGCGCUACUUUGAGCCACUGGUGAAAAAAGAACAAAUGGAAGAAAAGAUGAGAAACAUCAGAGAAGUGAAGUGCCGUGUCGUGACAUGCAAGACGUGCGCCUAUACCCACUUCAAGCUGCUGGAGACCUGCGUCAGUGAGCAGCAUGAAUACCACUGGCAUGAUGGUGUGAAGAGGUUUUUCAAAUGUCCCUGUGGAAACAGAAGCAUCUCCUUGGACAGACUCCCGAACAAGCACUGCAGUAACUGUGGCCUCUACAAAUGGGAACGGGACGGAAUGCUAAAGGAAAAGACUGGUCCAAAGAUAGGAGGAGAAACUCUGUUACCAAGAGGAGAAGAACAUGCUAAAUUUCUGAACAGCCUUAAAUAACCCGAACUUCAGACAUUUUCCCACAGACUUCCUGGCCUCCUGUGACUCUGGAAAGCAAAGGAUUGGCUGUGUAUUGUCCAUUGAUUCCUGAUUGACGCCGUCAAAAACAAAUGCUUGUUAAGCCCAUAAGCUUUGCCUGCUUACUUUCUGCCAUUGGGUUGGUUUGAUACCACAUUUAACAUUGACAUUUAAGUGGAAAACCAAGUUAUCAUUGUCUUUUCUAAGCUCAGUGUGGAUGAUUGCAUUACUUCAUUCACUGAAGUUUUUGCCCAAAAAUUGGAAGGUAAACAGAGAGCUAUGUUUCUGUAUCUUUUGGUUAUAGAGUGUUCACUUCUUUAUCAUAACAAAAUUCUAGUGUUUAUACGAACACCCAGAGGCAAAAGAAUUUGGCUUAAUUCUCACUCCAGGUAAGUAGCUUAACUUCUGGGCUUCAGUUUUCUCAUCUGUAAAAUCAGGAAGAUUGGACUAAGUGAUCCUGAAAUGUAUUUUUUAGCACUGGAUUUCUACAAAUAAUAAAACUUUCCCAUCUAGAUAAUGAUGAUCACAUAGUCUUGAUGUACGGACAUUAAAAGCCAGAUUUCUUCAUUCAAUUCUGUUAUCUCUGUUUUACUCUUUGAAAUUGAUCAAGCCACUGAAUCACUUUGCAUUUCAGUUUAUAUAUAUAGAGAGAAAGAAGGUGUCUGCUCUUACAUUAUUGUGGAGCCCUGUGAUAGAAAUAUGUAAAAUCUCAUAUUAUUUUUUUUUUAAUUUUUUUAUUUUUUAUGACAGGGUCUCACUAUGUCACCCUGGCUGGAGUGCAGUAGUGCGAUCGCGGCACACUGCAGCCUUGGCUUCCCUGGGCUCAAGCAGUCCUCCCACCUCAGUCUCCCAAAUAGCUAGGACUACAGGCGUGCGUGACCAAGCCCAGCUAAUUUUUGCAUUUUUUGUAGAGAUGGGGUUUUGCCAUGUUGCUCAGGCUGGUCUCAAACUCCUGAGCACUAGCAAUCCACCCACCUCUGUUUCCAAAAAAAAAAAAAAAAUGAAAGGUCAACCCCUAUGCAAAUUACCACAGCAAAGGUUUCAUUCAGGAGAUUCUUCCAUCUGGGCAACCUGGUUUUCCAAAUAUCAUUUGACCUAAGUGAAUGUUGAUACUAGCUAAAGAUUGGGUAAAUUGGUUGAAUUAUUGUAUUGAAGCUUGAGCUGUAGCUAAAAGUAAUUUAGGUUUCCCCUAAGAUGUUAUUAUGUUAGGGACAUAACACUUUUGGGAGGUUGUUGUGGGAGAUGGUUGAUUUAGGUUUUCAAAAGCUAGAAAUAAAAUUUACAUGCCUUAGAUUUCAUAAAAUUCUGCUCUAAUUGGGUGGAAGGUGCUGUAUCUAACUUGUGUUCCUCCUAAGGUUAUGUCCUAAUAACUAUUCUUUUAGGAGUAUACUUCUACUUUAUAGAAGGUUGCUUUUCUUUUUAAUUUUUUCUAACAAAGAAAAGAAUAAAGUAUUUAUUAAUAAGAACCAGAAAGCACUUGAAACUGAUGUUUUUAAUGGCUCAUUUAGGGUAGAUUUAUUUAUCUCAUUAACUUAAAACAGCUAUGUGUAUGAAAUAGGUCACAACAGAACUUGAACACCAGGUUGGUGUCUGAGCAAUCCCUUUCUUAUGGGAAAAACAAUGUUCUUGUUUGAACAGAGGGUAUCAUUGCAGUCAGUAUUCACGUGUAUAUUGUUAUAUAAGUUGUAUAAUAUGCUUGUAAAGGCUGAGGGUGAGCUGUAUCUGGAUGCCUUUUUACAAUUUGAUUUUAACUUUUAAAAUAAAUUUAAAACAUAAUUGUCA